CUUAGGGGGCUUAGGCCUGCCCUGUGGAGCAUCCCUGCGGGGAACUCCCGCCAGCUUGAGCGACGCGGAUCCUGCGAGCGCUCCUGGGUAGGCAAUUGCCCCGGUGGAACGCCUAGUCAGAGCAGUGCGUGGCAGGCCCCCGUGGAGUAUCAACGCAGUGGCUGAACACCGGGAAGGAACAGGCACUUGGAGUCCGGACAUUUGAAACUUGAGCACGGCUCUUUGCUGCUAAAGUUACCCGGAACGGGAGUCAUUAUGACCCUUACGGUCCCCCGAGAGGAGGAAUGGAGACUUUUGUUAACUGAGCCGGGCCAAGAGAUAAGACCAGCUCUGGCUAAGCGGUGGCCAAGAGUGUGGGCGGAAGACAACCUCCAGGGUUGGCAGUCAACGAAGCCCCCGUACUUAUAGAAGUUAAGCCCGGGGCCCAGCCGGUUAGGCAAAAACAGUACCUGGUCCCCAGAGAAGCUCUUGAAGGUAUCCAGGUCCAUCUCAAGCACCUAAGAACCUUUGGAAUUAUAGUUCCUUGUCAGUCUCCAUGGAACACUCCCCUCCUGCCUGUUCCCAAGCCUGGGACCAAGGACUACAGGCUGGUACAGGAUUUGCGCUUGGUUAAUCAGGCUACAGUGACUUUACAUCCAACAGUACCUAACCCGUACAUAUUGCUGGGGUUGCUGCCAGCUGAGGACAGCUGGUUCACCUGCUUGGACCUGAAAGACGCUUUCUUUAGCAUCAGAUUAGCCCCUGAGAGGCAGAAGCUGUUUGCCUUUCAGUGGGAAGAUCCGGAGUCAGGUGUCACUACUCAGUACACUUGGACCUGGCUUCCCCAAGGGUUCAAGAACUCCCCCACCAUCUUCGGGGAGGCAUUGGCUCGAGACCUCCAGAAGUUUCCCACCAGAGACCUAGGCUGCGUGUUGCUCCAGUACGUUGAUGACCUUUUGCUGGGACACCCCACGGCAGUCGGGUGCGCCAAGAGAACAGAUGCUCUACUCCGGCACCUGGAGGACUGUGGGUAUAAGGUGUCCAAGAAAAAAAGCUCAGAUCUGCCAACAGCAGGAAUGUUGCAUAGAACGACCGCCUCUUCGGCUGCGUGGCUUCGGAGCAGCUUUGACUACAACUCCCAGACUGCAUCGCCCCUGCCCCCCCACUUCCGGAGCUGACUUCACUUCGAGGAACCUUUUCCCUCCAGGAAUCAAGGAUUUUCUUUUGCUUUGUGGCCGGAUUUUGCUACUGCUUGCUCUUCUUACUUUAACUAUUUCUGUGACUACCUCAUGGCUUAACUCAUUUAAAUCUCCCCAAGUUUAUCUGAAGGAAGAAGAAGAAAAGAAUGAGAAAAGACAAAAACUUGUGAGAAAAAAACAACAAGAAGCACAAGGAGAGAAGGCCAGCAGAUACAUAGAGAAUGUUUUAAAACCUCACCAGGAAAUGAAAUUGAGAAAACUGGAGGAGCGCUUUUAUCAAAUGACGGGUGAAGCCUGGAAAUUAAGCAGUGGUCACAAACUUGGGGGUGAUGAAGGUACAAGUCAGACAUCUUUUGAAACAUCAAACAGAGAAGCAGCAAAGAGCCAGAACUUGCCUAAACCUUUAACUGAAUUUCCGUCUCCUGCUGAACAGCCCACAUGCAAGGAGAUUCCUGAUUUACCUGAAGAACCUUCUCAAACAGCAGAAGAAGUAGUUACUGUUGCUCUCCGAUGUCCCAGUGGGAAUGUCCUGAGGAGAAGGUUUUUGAAGUCCUACAGCUCACAGGUCUUAUUUGACUGGAUGACGAGAAUUGGGUACCACAUAUCUCUAUACAGCCUUUCUACUUCCUUUCCCAGACGGCCUCUGGCAGUGGAGGGAGGCCAGUCGCUGGAGGACAUAGGAAUAACUGUGGACACUGUACUCAUCCUGGAGGAGAAGGAGCAGACCAACUAGGAAAGAAGGGAGAGCUCCCUGUUUGCAUGAAGUCAGUUAUGCUAUGACCUUCUGGCACAAUAAAGGCUUCACUUUCAAAUCACACUAUACCUUGAUUGAGCUCAUGGCAGUAAACUUUGAACAUUGAUAUCCAUGGGAAUAGGAUUAGAAAAGGAUUGCUUUCUAUAUAUAAUAAUCUGUGGACUGUGCCAUUUUACAGUGUACCAAAUGAGAAUGAGGUUGAAAUGUAUGCAGUAAGGUACUCAGUAAUUAAUUGGUAUUUUUUCCCAGCUGACAUGAUUUCUCAGUGUUAGAAAACAAACCCUUAGAACUUUCCUUUCUGCCUCUUCAAUCCAUCUUACCACACAAUAUUUCAUGAUUCAAAUUCUUCAAAGUCUUAUACGCAGGAAUGUUUAUUCUGCUGUAUUUCUGUGAAAUUAAAAACUUGGAAGAAGCUUCAAAGCUCUUGGAGGCUUUAAAGUUCUUUCUGUUGGGUGUGCAUUACAGUUUACUUAACUGAUGUUUGCGAUUUAUAUAAUUUUGCCUUGUAUUAAAUGUUACAAAGUUCCAAAUGAAUCAGUAUUUUAAAAAAUAAAACUAUGAAAGCAUUAAAAUAUAGGUGAAUUUUUAAAA